GAGACAGAGUCUUGCUGUGUUGCCCCAGCUGAAGUGCAGUGGCACAGUCUUGGCUCACUGUAACCUCUGCCUCCCGGGUUCAAAUAAUUCUCAUGCCUCAGCCCCCCAAGUAGCUGGGACUACAGGUGCCCACCACCAUGCCUGGCUAAUUUUUUGUAUUUUAGUAGAGAUGGAGUUUCACCGUGUUGCCCAGGCUGGUCUCAAACUCCUGACCUCAGUCAGUCCAUCCGCCUCAGCCUCCCAAAGUGCUAGGAUUCCAGGCGUGAGCCACUGCUGCUCGGCCAGGGUCCUUAAGUUCAAAUCAUGGAGCAGUCCACAGAGCACUCUUCUCAGGUGCAGAGUGGAAAGGACUUUGAUCGUGGACUAGUAUUUUUAGUCACAUCCACAGGCCUUUGAAAGGGAAAAAAUAUAUUAUUGAUAGGUCCUGUUUUUUGAGGAAAAAAAAAAAACAAGCAUUCCUAACUACCUGGCAAAUAAUUUCUUCUAUUCUAAUGAUAAUUAAUUUAUGUGGUCAAAGAUCAGAGAAAGGGAGCCAUAGGCAGGACAGCAGCCCAGUAUUGGUACCACACUCUUAGGGAUCUCUUAAUUUUUGUUUUCUUCAUAACAAUUGUCAGUUUUCUUACACUGUGCUGUAUUUGGAGUGGAUGAUGCUGGUGGUGAUUGUCUAAAACUUAGAUAUUUAAACAGUUUGAAAACUUGUUGGAGUAGGAAUUAUAAAAGCUUUAUAGUUUUCAUUAUCUUCUCCAUUCCCACUCUUCCAAGUUACUACAAAUAUGCCUAAUUUUUAUAAAUAUAUGCAAUUUAAAAUGUUUUAAUUGUAAUAUACAAGUAGUUCUUGGCAGUAGAUUCCUUCGGAGAUUUUUCUUCAUAUUUUAUAGAGUUCUUCAGAUUUUUUCCUCUUUGCUUAUAAUACUUAUAAAGUUAUAUUUAUUUUCUUUUGUCUAAACUCAUUCAAUGUGCAUUUUUCUCACCUGCUCUUUUGUUUGCUUGCUGCGAUACAAGGCUGUAUAAAGAAAUACUUGGUGCUUUCUGUGACAGCAGGCCAUAUAAAGAAAUACGAACUCUUUUUUUUCUUUUUGAGAUAGAGGCUGGAGCACUAUGGCGCCAUCUUGACUUACUGCAACCUCUGUCUCCCAGGUUCAAGCGAUUCUCCUGCCUUAGCCUCCCGAGUAGCUGAGAUUACAGGUGCCCAUCACCACACCCGGCCAAUUUUUUGAGAUGGAGUCUUGCUCUGUUGCCCAGGCUGGAGUGCAGUGGCAUGAUCUCAGCUCAUUGCAACCUCUACCUUCUGGGUUCAAGCAAUUCUCCAGCCUCAGCCCCCCGAGUAGCUAGGAUUACAGGUGUGCACCACCACGCUCAGGUAAUUGUUUUAUUUUUUAGUAGAGACGGGGUUUUGCCGUGUUGGCCAGGCUGGUCUCAAACUCCUGGCCUCAGGUGAUCCACCCACCUUGGCCUCCCGGAGUGCUGGGAUUACAGUUAUGAGCCACCGCACCCGGCCAUUUUUUUGUAUUUUUAGUAGAGAUGAGGUUUCACCAUGUUGGCCAGGUUGGUCUCAAACUCCUGACCUCAAGUGAUCUGCCUGCCUCAGCCUCCCAAAGUGCUGGGAUUACAGGUGUGAACAACCGCAGCUGGCCAAGAAAUACCAGCUCUUACCAAGCACUUUAAUUCAUUUAGUUUUUCACUCUGGCUACAGUGAGAAAAGACAAUGUUUUUACACUUGAUAUACUUUUUAUAAGAAAAAAUCAAUGCAGGAUGAAAAUAUCCUGUUGCUCUAGUAAUUCCCACAGAAGGUCAGCCUCAAUAAUAGAAGAUGAAAAAAGUUUUGUGGUGUUUGCUGUUUUAUAAACUCAUAUUUGGAGAAGGAACACAAUAUAUAUAUGAUUUCCUCAUAACUGCUGUUGGUGCCCCAGAUUUGAUAUUGUUGCAUGAUAACCUGACAUUGCUUCCUGCUUCUGAAGGAAUGAUUGGAUUUGAAGCCAACAUGCUUGCUAAACCGGGAAGCUGCUAUUACAGAAGGCACAGGAAGUCAAGCUGCCUAUGCAGUUGUGCUGAGACAUGAGACUCAUACGUUGUGACCCGUGCCUAUUGUAUGUCUCCCCAUCUUUAUAACUGCUUUUGAAAACUGGCUUCAAAUAAGCAAAAGGCCUAGUGUUAUUUCCAUAGCAGCACUAAAAUUAAUGAAUAAGAGUUACAGAGUUGGCUGAAUAUAAAGGAGAUAUGUCUAACAAUUACAGUUCUCCAAAACCUAGUGUGCUCCCUCUUUGUCCUUGUAAGUGGUCAAACAAAAAUGGCAUAAGCACUCACUUAGGUGUUGCAUUGGUCAGGGACCUGGUGGGAGGCGGAUGGCACACACAAGUUGGAUAAUUUGGGGAACAUUUCAUAAAAAGACAGUAAAAAUGUAGGGUAUAGUAAGAAUAUACAAGGGCAAGUAAAAGGGUAUGGGGCAAGGGCUAAUAUCUGUACGUGAGGAAGAAAGAGGAGGAAAUGUUAUCAAACCACUGGCUGUGUACAAAUGGCUGCCUUAUAGGAGCUGAGGUCUGCAGUCAAGGGAGACUGUCCACUGAGAACAUACAGGGACACAGCCAGCAGUUCUGUUCCCUGACCCUGGGCUCUUCUGUCUCCAGCCAUUGUCCCUUUUGACUAAACACAACCAGUGUAGAACAAGGAUUGUUGCAGUCCUUGACAGAUCAGACUCUUCAGGCUCAAAGAGUACAAAUAGGUGGGGAGUAGAUUGGAGUUAAGUGGAAACAGUCCUGUGCAGAUGUUAUAGUGAGUGGGAUAUCCCUGCUGUCCUCAUUGAUAGUACAGAACUCUUUUUUUUUUAAAUUAAAGUUCUAGGGUACAUGUGCACAACGUGCAAGUUUGUUACAUAUGUAUACGUGUGCCAUGUUGGUGUGCUGCACCCAUUAACUCGUCAUUUACAUUAGGUAUAUCUCCUAAUGCUAUCUCUCCCCGCUCCCCUGACCCCACAACAGGCCCCGGGGUGUGAUGUUCCCUGCCCUGUGUCCACAUGUUCUCAUUGUUCAGUUCCCACCUAUGAGUGAGAACAUGCAGUGUUUGGUUUUCUGUCCUUGCGAUAGUUUGCUCAGAAUGAUGGUUUCCAGCUUCAUCCAUGUCACUACAAAGGACAUGAACUCAUCCUUUUUUAUGGCUGCAUAGUAUUCCAUGGUGUAUAUGUGCCACAUUUUCUUAAUCUAGUCUAUCAUUGAUGGACAUUUGGGUUGGUUCCAAGUCUUUACUAUUGUGAAUAGUGACGCAAUAAACAUAUGUCCGCAUGUGUCUUUAUAGCAGCAUGAUUUAUAUUCCUUUGGGUAUAUACCCAGUAAUGGGAUGGCUGGGUCAAAUGGUAUUUCUAGUUCUAGAUCCCUGAGGAAUCGCCACACUGACUUCCACAAUGGUUGAACUAGUUUACAGUCCCACCAACAGUGGAAAAGUGUUCCUAUUUCUCCACAUCCUCUCCAGCACCUGUUGUUUCCUGACUUUUUAAUGAUCGCCAUUCUAACUGGUGUGAGAUGGUAUCUCAUUGUGGUUUUGAUUUGCAUUUCUCUGAUGGCCAGUGAUGAUGAGCAUUUUUUCAUGUGUCUGUUGGCUGCAUAAAUGUCUCCUUUUGAGAAGUGUCUGUUCAUAUCCUUCACCCACUUUUUGAUGGGGUUGUUUGAUUUUUUCUUGUAAAUUUGUUUAAGUUCUUUGUAGAUUCUGGAUAUUUGCCCUUUGUCCGAUGGGUAGAUUGUAAAAAUUUUCUCCCAUUCUGUAGGUUGCCUGUUCACUCUGAUGGUAGUUUCUUUUGCUGUGCAGAAGCUCUUUAGUUUAAUUAGAUCCCAUUUGUCAAUUUUGGCUUUUGUUGCCAUUGCUUUUGGUGUUUUAGUCUUGAAGUCCUUGCCCAUGCCUAUGUUCUGAAUGGUAUUGCGUAGGUUUUCUUCUAGGGUUUUUAUGGUUUUAGGUCUAACAUUUAAGUCUUUAAUCCAUCUUGAAUUAAUUUUUGUAUAAGGUGUGAGGAAGGGAUCCAGUUUCAGCUUUCUACAUGUGGCUAGCCAGUUUUCCUAACACCAUUUAUUAAAUAGGGUAUCCUUUCCCGAUUUCUUGUUUUUGUCAGGUUUGUCAAAGAUCACAUGGUUGUAGAUUUGUGGUAUUAUUUCUGAGGGCUCUGUACAGAACUCGUUUUUAUGAAGAAUCAUUGACUUUCAAAAAUACUUGAGGUUACCCAGUUCAAGCAUCCAAAAAUACAGACUUCCUGUUCAUUCAGCAUCUAGUUUAAUGUAUUCAAUUAUGGAGAGCAAAAUUUUACAUUAUGAAACAUCUUGGCUGGGCACGGUGGCUAGUGCCUGUAAUCCUGGCACUUUUGGAGCCCCAGGUGGGUGGAUCACUUGAGGUCAGGAGUUCAAGACCAGCCUGGCCAACAUGGUGAAACCCCAUCUCAGUUUAAAAAAAAAAGAUGUAUCUUGUUCCAUUGUUGAACAACUGUAGAAGGUUAUUCUUGCAUUGAAAUGUUCCUUCCUGUACCUUCUGUUGCUUGCUAGUUCUUCCGUUUGCUAUUCUCUUGCCUUCUGUCUUUUGGUCCCUUUAUGACAUUUUUGGUGUUUGUUUAACAGGCAUUCACUUAUUCAACAUCUAUUUAUUGAAUGCUUGCUGUAGGCCAGGACUUGUUCUUGGUGCUGGGUAUUCAGCUGUGAACAAGACAAAGCUUCUGCCUUACAUGAAACUUACAUUGUAGUAGGUAGAGACAGACAUUAAGCAAAUACAUAAUAUGGUCUCUGUAGGUGAUAACUACUGAGAUUAACAGCAGUUAACCAUGGUCACAAGAGAAAACUGUGGCUUAAAUUGGGUCUGAAGUCAUUCUGAGUCAACUGUGUAAUGCAGUGGCCAAAAAGCCUAAAUUCAUCUUAGACUAUUUGAAUCAAAUGGCCAUGUUAGAGAGGUCAUGUUUGCUUUCUUAUUGUCAAGCUGAGCCUGGUGUAUAGCAUUUACUUUUUGAAGAGAUAUUGGCAAGUGGAAACUUGUUCAGGGGUAUCCCCAUGAUAGCCUUGUAAACAGCUGAAGAAAGCCAUCAUAUUUGCAUGGAGUGUUCCCUAGGCCAAACCUUUCUGGUUUUGCCAACAGUUUCUCAAAUGGUAUGAUGUCUAUACUCUUUAACUGUCCUGGUCUUCCUCCAGAUAAUUAAUUUCCUCUUAAAAUGAUGCUCCCAGAAUUCAACUCAUCUUUCCAGAUGUGGUUUCAACUUAGGUAAUGCUUAUUAGACUAUUUCUUCCCUUGAUCUGGUUAUUUAAUUUUAGUAACGCAUCUGAGGAUUGAAUUUCCUUUAAAAACACACACACACACACACACACACACACACACACAUCUGUGUUACUUGACUCUCAGUGUUGAGCUAGGCUGUAAAGCCAGGUCUCCAGCACUUCUGUUCGUACAAUUUAUGUACAUAAAUAUGUUACCCAGCAUCUCUAUUAAAAUGUCAUCUCAUCGCUGUCUGUGCAGUAUUCUACAUUAAGAUCCUUUGGAAUAUUGUCUUUCAUCUAACUUGGUGUUGUCUACAUAAUUAACAAGCAUAUUCUCAAACUUCAUCUAGGUGUUUAAUAUAAUUGUUUAAUUAAAAAAGAAUAAUAGCACCAGACCUUUCCUUCAGAUUAUAGCAGCUCAAUAAUUAAUCCUGUUUUAGUAUGACAUUUCAAAUAACUGUGAACAGCCUUAAUAUGUCAUCCAUUUUACAUUUCUGCAUUUUAUCCAAACAUUUUGAAAAAUGAAGAUACAGUCUUCAUUUCAUGAUGGCAUUUCUAUCUGGUACUAGGCUUAACAAAAAACAUACUAGAAGCCAGGCUUGGUGGCUCACGCCUAUAACCCUAGCACUUUGGGAGGCCAAGGUAGGCAGAUCACUUGAGCUCAGGAGUUUGAGACCAGCCUGGGCAACAUGGCAAAAAUGCAAAUCCACAAAAAAUCCAAAAAUUAGCCGGCCAUGGUGGCAUGCGCCUGUAGUCCCAGCUGCUUGGGAGACUGAGGCACAAGAAUUGCUUGUGCCAGGAAGGCAGAGGUUGCAGUGAGCCGAGAUUGCACCAUUGCACUCCAGCCUGGGUGAUGGGAGUGAAACCCUCUCUCUCUCUCUCUCUCUCUCUCUCUCUCUCUGUAAAUAAAUAAAUAUAUAUAUAUAUAUAUUUUUACCUUUCUAACAUUGCAGGGAGUGACCUUUCUUUUUCAUUCAGUCUCAGUUAUGUGUCCAAAGCAUUGGUAUAUGUUUUGGUUUAGUUUUUAAUUUGCAAGCUCCAUGUAAGACUACAGUGGGUUUUUUGUCAGAUGCCUCCUUAUUUAUGAGUUGGAGUGAAGACAGGGAGAGUAUUGACCUCAUUCUUCCUGGAGAUCUUUUUUGUUUUCCAAGGAGUUUGGUGUCGUAUUUUAUAGGAUUUUCUAGAUUAUAUGUAUAACAUCUUGACUCCACUCAAAUGCCCAAGAACCCAUACAUUUUGGUGGCAGCAUGACUUUCAAGAGGAGUUGCUUCUCUUGCUUAGUACAAAGUGUCCAUGGAUCAGAAUGUGAUUAAACAAGUCAAGUCAGGUGACUUGUCACUGAGGGUUUGUAUUGGUUGCAAGUACCAGAAAUGUGCCUGUGCCGAUUGGGGAAUCAGGAUAUUAGUCAAAGGAAAGGAAAACCUGUUCAACAAUUUUUCUUGCUUUUCAUGUGCUGCAGAGAAAAGGCUAAAUCCCAUCUGGUGCACACUAUUGUGGGAAUCUUAUACUUUAGAUUCAUAAACACAGUAUGUUCAGAUUUUCUAGAUUUGACAUUUGCUUGAAUGUGUUCGGUGUGUAUUUUAUACUGAGUGUCAAAUUUCUUGCCUUUUGACGAUAGCUGACUUUUAGUUGACUAAAAAAGUAGUAGUCAUAGUUAGGUUUACUAUCUGUGGCUAUCACAGGGUUCACAUGGGCAUCAUUGUCCAACCAAAGUUGCUUCUGAAGUGCUGCCAUACAGUCUUGGCUCUCAUGAACACUUGUCCUAGUUUUUACCGUUGUCCUGGAAGAAUUACUUUCACGAGUGUCUGGGUUUGGAGGAAAAAUUGUAUGGCUCCUAUGGAUACGUCUCAAAGUAUUCUAGGAAGCAAGUUGUUCCCAUUGUGCAGUUAUUGCUUUGACAUCUGGCCUUCCUUACUUACCUCUGCUACAGAAAGAAUCCAGAAUGACUUGUAAGGCUGGUAAACCCAGUGAUUCUUGGAAUACUUUUUCAAGAAUGCUCCUCCAGGAAUGCUCUUGGAGUCUCACUCUGUAGCCCAAGCUUGAGUGCAGUCGUGUGAUCCUGGCUCACUGCAACCUCCGCCCCCUGGGCUCAAGGGAUUCUCAUGCUUCAGCCUCCUGAAUAGCUGGAAUUAUAGGUGCCCGCCACAACGCCUGGCUAAGUUUUUGUAUUUUACUAGAGACGGGGUUUCACCAUGUUGCCCAAGGUGGUCUUGAACUCCUGAGCUCAGGCGAUGUGCCCGCCUUGGCCUCCCAAAGUGCUGGGAUUACAGGCAUCAGCCACUGCACCCGGCCUGAAAACACAUUUUCUUAAUGGGACUAAACUUUUCUAGCUGAAUUGAUCUAUUUUAAAACUUGCCAAUGAAAGCUCCUUAGUAGUAUCUGCUAAUUAAAUGCAGUUUUUAUACCUAACGGACCUUUUAAAGAAUGUGUGCACUUUGCAAACCCCAUUGCUUCUUGCCGUAUCUGAGCACUUGCCACCUGGUGGUAAGGAGACCAUUCCAUCUCCUUCACUAGAUGGUAGCACCUGGAAGUCAGGGAUCAUUGCUGACUUAUCUUGCCUCCCAACAUUGAUCAUGCAGUAGGUGUGGAUGAGAAAGAGGGAGAUAAGGGAAGAAAGGGGGCUGUGAAUAAACGCUGUUGCUUUCUGCUUCCUUUUUAGGAGUUAAAAGUCUCUUCAGCUACCUGUUUAGGAGUAUGAAAGCAAAUCUAGGAAAUGGCCUCUGCAGUUUUCCGAAUAUGACAAAUCAUUUAGUUUCCUAAGCUUGUUACUCUACAGUGGGACUUCUCAACCUCUGCACUGUUGAUAUUGUGGCCUGGAUGAUUGUUUGUUGUGUGGCCUGCCCUGUGCAUUAUAGGGUGUUUAGUUAGCAGCAGCAUCCUUGGUCUCUGCCCACUAGAUGCCAGUAGUGCACCCCAUCCCCAGCUGUGACAACAAAAAUGUCUGCAGGCAUUGCCAAGUGUGCCCUGGAGGCAAAAUAGCCGCCCCCUAAUUGAGAUUGAGAACCGCUGCUGCAUAGGAGCUCCUGUCUGGGACAAAUGCCCACCAGAGAAACCAGCAAGUAAUAGAAAUGUGGCUUUGGAAGGGAACUUAGAAAUCAUCUGGAAUGUUGUAUCCUGGAGAACUCCUCGCCCCACACCAGCGCCAGCACCCCUCCCCAACCCCCUACACCACCUCCACCUUUAUACUUAUGCUUUAUACCUGCAGAACUAUAACCUAAGGGAAGGAAUGAAUAUAAAAAAGAAAAAAAUACAACUAUAUGAGGUAAUACUGUUUAGGGCUUGUAGGGUUAUUUGUUUUAAGUUUGCUUACAGAUCAUGAACAUGUGUCUACUUUCAGGUUACUCAAAAUAAGAAAGCAUAAGCUUAUAGAAAUAGGUCAGGGAGAAAAACACAGAAAAACUAAUGUGCAGCACUACUAAAAAAGAAUUCAAGGUGUAUGUUGAACAUUUUUCAGAUUAAAAAGAACUCACUGGAAUGUGGCUGGAUUGCUAGUAUCGCCCUGUGGAGCUAUCUGGGCUUCAUAUGAGGCUAUUCUAAGUACAUGCAUCAAAAAAGAGAUAUAGAAGAGUAUUUAAAGUAAUGAUAAUUGGCCUUUUUCAAAAAAUGACUUGCUUUCUAAACCUGAAAAAUAGCCAUCAUGAUACUAGAGAAAUAGCUGAGAUAUUAAUAUUUCCUCUGUAGAUUGUUUUGUUUUAUAAGGGCAUUUUGUGUCUUACUAAGAAAUCUCACAUAAAAGUAAGAACACCAAAUUAAAUAUUAGCUCUUGUGGUUAUUUUAAGACUCAUCUCAAUAACCAAGAGAAUUUGGUUCUCACACUUUGUACCUUUUGAUUGUAAACAGCUUUAAACAGGUUUAUGUUGUACUUCAUCAAAAAUUAUAGAGGAUCUGCAGACUGAGACGCAUUGGGACUGAAAUUAGGCAAUUCAGAGUUUCUCAUGCAUGUAAGCUGCUUUUAUUUUGAUCCCUAUCAUUCUUAGUCUGUCUUUUCAAAUAUUCUACUGGAAGGACUGUUGUGAGUUGAGGGCAAAGGAGAAAAUGGCAGGGUCUCGAGCCACCAGGCCUCAUAAUACCUGCUCUUUGAGGUAGAGUAAAAGCUAACUGAUGAAUGUUUUCCAGAAUAAUAUUUAGAUUUAGUCUGGUGGUUUUUUUUUUUUUCUUGUUUUGUUUGCUUUGGUUUAAGCUCAAUACAGUCACAUCUGAAUUUACACAACAAAAAUGUUUCCGAAAAGUUGUGGAUGAAUCCAUUUUUAAUAAGCCAAGUACUAUAAAAAGCAUCAGAAGAACUUGUUAACUGAACUUAUCCUAAUGUUCUGAUCACCUGUUUCUUUUAAUAGACAUAGUGGUUGCAACAAUGCUUUGAUUAGUUCCUUUUUGGAAGCUGGCUUUUGUUGGGGGGAGGGUUUUUGUUUCUUGUAUCUUAAACUUGACACCUUGAUUCUCAUUGAAAAAACUUUCAACCAUGUAUGGUUGGUGAUUUGUUGAAAUUUAUAACUGAAAAUCUGCCACUCUGCUUUUAGUAUUUGAAAUGCCUUGGCAGGGAGACGUUUUUCUCAGAACAGAUCUUUUGGAGGACCUCAGGAAGUUAAUUAUUCUGGCAAGAAGUUCUUUUUGAACUUUUUUGGAUCAUUAUGAUAUUAUGCUAAUUUAUCUAAAAAAUGGAUUCUAAGUUGAAUAACUGUAUAGUCCUGGCAGAUAAGAGCAUGUCAGAUGUCUUGGCACAGUUUGGGGACAGAGGGGACUUUCCCACUUCUUUAUGUAAUCCACCAUCAUAAUGUGGGAGUUUUAUGAAAUUUCUUCUGUUAUACAGAAAUACUUAGCUUUUUAGGCCGUAUGUGCUGCUCAGUGAAAACAAGCUCUGUGUAUGUCUGUAUAUGUUUAAAUGAAAUGAAAAAGAGAAGUGAAAUCCAAGAAAUUUCUGGUUUGCAGUGGUGAUUAUUUUUAGCCACGUUCAUGUGUUUUAAACAAUCCCUUUUAGGUCUGUUGAAUGUAGCUUGGAACAGAACGUCCCAUAGAAAUGAUAGUAUAGUACACGUGGUGGCAAAGUUUCCAUAUUAGCCCUCAAAGAUUAUUUAACUCAUCAUAUACUCACACGCUUUGCCGUACAAGGGGCAAUGAUGUAUAGCGUAUAAAAACACUGUUUAAUAAUACUCAACCUACAGCAACUUUCAAUACUAAGAAUGAAAUAAAAUUGAAAAAUUGUAAAAAUGCAUAAGGAUAAAUUUUGUUUCUCUGAAAAGGUUGCUUUUGAGGAAAAGUAGUUUUAAAGAGACUUGGUGGUGUGGUAGAAGAACUCCCAGCAGACCUGAAGAUGUAGCAGAUGUAUAGCAGUUUGGGCAUCUUGGACAAGUAAAUCAUACUCGCAAGCCUCAGUUUCUUUUAAUGUCAUGGGGAUAGUUGUGUGGAUCAGAGCAGAAUUUGUGUGAAGGUGAUUUGCAAACUGUAAAGUCCUAUGCAAAUAUACAAUAUAUGUUCUGGUUCUUUUCUUAAUUAUGAAAAUCUUGUAUCCUGGCCUUUUUCUUGACACUCAUAUAUUAGUAACAAAAAUCUUUAUGCUUAGCAACAAUUAGUAAGGUCCUAUUUCGCUCACAAAUACAAUAAAUGCAUGUUAUUUUGACCUACAUGGAUGAUAGAAACAUUUGCUUUUUUGUGACAGCCUAUUGGAACUUCCAAAGUGUCUCUCUCUCUCUCUCUCUCUCUCUCUCUCUCUCUCUCUCUCUCGUUUUUCUAGUCUCUAAACCUCUCUUGUUUUUUCUUUGUCUGAGUAUCUUUCUGAACCACCGUCUCAAGUUUCAGGUUAUACGACAGAGCUCAUACUCCAAGCCCUGGCCUCUCUCUGACCUUGUGCCUCUGGCCUGGGACAAGCUUCACACUGCCAGACUCUGCAGCUGACCCUUUGUAUCUCCCAGUAGUCUGAGCAGCAUUCAUUUGCUCAAGGUCUCACCAGAGACCAAACAGGGGCAGCCUCUCUGGAGAGACCAUGGCCUCCCAACAGUAUUUUUGAUGUCAGUGGCCUAGCCUUAGGCCCCGAAGCCAGGAACUAGAUGUGAUAGGGGCCAAAUCCCCCAAACCCGAGGAGCUUUUCUGGUAGAAAAUGUGUUAUGAAAAAAAGGGGGACUCAGUGGCCAUUGCAGACCAAAGCCUCAUUCAUUGAGGUGGGGUAGGGGUUGCUGGGGACUACAAUUCAGAGUUAUAUAUGUAACAGAGUUAUGCAUAUAAUUCAGCAAACAAAGAGGCAAGUUGAAAAGGGUUUAUUAAAGUAUUAAUGUUUGUGUCAAAUGUAUAAAAUUCAGGAAACAGGCAGAGCAAUAACAUUUAAUGUUGGAAGAGGACUUAGAGAUACAAAAAAUAGAGUUUAUUCAUUCUGGAGCAGAGAAAUCUUAAGCCGGAUAGGUUAACUGAUUUGCAAGUGUCUCCUGCCUUCCAAUCCUGCAUCCUUAAGGAUAUCCUUAAGAUGAUACAUCUGGGUUUUGCGAUGCUCUGUUCUCCAGGUACGGUUAGCAGUGAUUUUGCAUAACUAUGUGCUGAGACCCUAGGAUCUAACAAACUAUAAAGGUUAGAAAUGAAAUAUGAGGUAGCCUACUAUAUCAGCCACCUCUGAUUCCCUUCUCCCACCACAGGGAGAAUUAGAUUGACCGGCUGAUCGAUUGCUUGAUUGAGACAGGAUCUUGCUCUGUCACCCAAGCUAGCCUGCAGUGAUCUCCACUCACUGCAGCCUCGACCUCCUGGGCUCAAGUGAUCUUCCCACCUCAGUCUCCUGAGUAGCUGGCACUACAUGUGCACACCACAGUGCCCGGCUAAUUUUUUGUAUGUUUUGUAGAGACAGGAUUUUGCCAUGUUGCCCAGGCUGGCCUUGAACUCCUGGGCUCAAGCUAUCCUGCCUUGGCCUCUCAAAGUGCUGGGAUGACAGAUGUGAGCCACUGUGCCUGGCCAGUAAUAUGUAUUAAGUAAGGUAAUUUGUAGGAGCUUAGAGAGAACCAGCAAUAUGACACAGUUUCUGCUCUUUUGGGGCUUACAAUACAGUAUUAUAUCAUCAGAGGGGGUCCAUUCUGAACCAUACCUUGAAUUAGGCAUUAGCAUACUAGAUUCUAAUUUUGUUUCUUCCAUUGAAUUUCUAACGUGGACCCUGGUUAAGUCUAAGAGAUCAUUUAAAUCGUGGGCCUCAGUUUUUUUAUUCAUAAAAUGAGAAUAUUGACAUGGGCCUCAGUUUUUUUAUUCAUAAAAUGAGAAUAUUGAAUCUUGAAACCCUGUUAUUUUUACAUUCUGUGUACAAAAGUCUCAUGGUACUAUCUUUAAUUUUACUUAUCAGAUUUUGAAUCUCUAGUGCUCUUUUUAUUUCAAGAUAUUCUUAGCCAAGCUAUAAAAUCAAACUAAUUUAUAUGCUGUUAUGAGGCAACUUAGCAAUUCAUAUAACCACAGGCUAGAGAAAGUUUGGACAUAUAUAAUGGUUCAUUUCUUCAAUUUUAAGGCAGAACUACAUCCCAAGCUUAUGUAAAAUAAUUUGAAUUAUUAUAUAUUCCCAUAGUUCUGCCUCAAAUAAAAUAUAACUGUUUUUGAAAAUUCAAAGACUUAGAAAGUAAAUUAGAGGAUUGUUUAUUAUAAAAGAACUUUGGACCCUACAAAGGAAUUUAACCACAGUUUUCUUUUCUUUGUUAAUAGAGUCUCACUGUGUUGCCCAGAUUGGUCUUGAACUCCUGGCCUCAAGUGAUCCUCUUUCCUUGCCCUCCCAAAGUGCUGGGAUUACAGGCUUGAGCCACCACUCCCAGCCAACAGAAUUCUUUUCAACAUAGAAGAUUUUGAAAAUUCUGAGAAGUGUAAGAAAAGAAAAAUUACUUGUAACUCUACUACUCAGAGAAAAACUGCUGUUAAAAUAUUGAGGUAUUUACUUCCAGACUGAUUUUUCUAUACAUAUUUAUAUAGCUAUAUAUAGUUAUUCUUUUGUAAGAGUGACUAUAAACUGUUUUGAAACUGGCUUUUUUAACAUAACAAUAUAUGUGAGCACAUUUUCCACAUCCCCAAAUAUUUUUGAAAAAUAUUUCUUUUAAAUAUCUGCAUAGUUUUGUACCCAUUAUAAUUUGGCUCUGGAAGAAGUUCAAGAUAUGCCAAAUAGUCUUGGCACAAUGGCUCACACCUGUAAUUCUGACACUUUUGGGGGCCGAGGUAGGAGGAUCACUUGAGGCCAGGAGUUCGAGACCAGCUUGGUCAACCUAGCAAGAGCUAUUUCCACAAAAAAGUGAAAAAACUACCCGGGCGUGGUAACACUCCCAUAGUCCUAGCUACUUAGGAGGCUGAGGUCAAAGGAUUGCUUGAGCCCAGGAGUUUGAGGCUGCAGUGAGCUAUGGUCGCACCACUGCACUCCAGCCUGGGUGACAGAGCAAGACCUUGUCUCUAAAAAGAAAAAAAAAAGAUAUGUGAAAUUAAAAAGUCCACUUUGGUGAUAAGGUCUUCCUUCUAAAUUAUAGAAAUAAUUGGCUUAAAAGGGAAAUUGAGAACAUGCUAACUUUGUGCUUUAUUCAAGAUAGACUUGUUUAUUCUUUGCUGCAUUUCUAUAACAAAACAUUUCAGCUGUAUAAUCCUUGGUAUAGCAAUGACUAGUUAUAAUAAUUAAUUUUUAAUUAGCUGUUCAUGAAGUUUUCAAAACAUCAACUUUUAUCGCAUUAAAAAAGUGAAAUAAUUUUGAAACAUUUCUUUCCUUUAAAUUUGAAGUAAGGUUAAAGUUUUUUGCAACCAAAUUUGGGGUUCAUCUACCAUGGUAAGUUGGUGCUAUUGGCUGUGCUAUAAUUUCAGGGUGAACUUGACUUUCCUUGAGUUUCCAGGCUGUACAGGACAGGAAAGGCUGUGGCCGUCAGGGAAAUGGAGCCAGAUGGUCCUCAUGAUCGAUGCCAAGCUCCCAACAGAGACAAAUGCUACACCCGACAGACUAGGGGCAACAGCACAUGUUAGGGUGAUUGCUCACCCUUUCCUGGAGAGGGGAGAGCUCUUCCCUUCUGCUGGUGUAUUUUGCAGCUAGUUUUUGCAGGCUCUGUUCAGUCUGGUGUAGCAAGUGUCCAGGCAGUUAACUUCUAAUGGGCAGUGAAGGAGGAGGUGAUGGCAGUAGCUGGGGCCGAGUUGGCAGCUAGUAGGGCUGUCUGAUGAAAUCCACAUUUUGGCAUCCUUGAAGUCUUUCAAAGGAAUCUGACUAAGUCACUUAACCUUGUGUCAUUUUGGUUUACUUGGCUUUUAAAGGGUAGUGGUAAUUAAACCAAUGGGAGCCAUUAGUUAGUAGAUCUUAGUGGCAGUUUUCAGUUUAAAAAUGGAAACCUACAGUCACAGAGCCAUUGACUCGUAAUAACACAGUGGCUUGUCCUUGACCCAAGGGAGUUGAUUUGGGGAAAUGAACAUAUCUGAGAGUCCUGUGUCCUGAGUUUAUAUAUCAGCAUAGCUACUUAGGAGCAGUAUCACUUUGGGCAUAUUUCUUAACCUCUCUGAAUCUCCUCUGUAAAAAUAAUCAUAAUUCUUCAAAACAUAAGUGAGAGCUUAUAUUUUAUAUAAGUAUGUGGCACAGUUAUUAGUUCCUCACUAGAUAUUAAUUAGUUCCUAUGAAAAUGAUAGAUUAGUGCCAAGUCAUCUGACCUCCCUGUGUAGGCUUAUUAUUGAUCACUGGGGGUCUGUAGCCCUGGAACAGUGUUUUCUUUUCUGAAUUAAUUACAGCCUCAUGUACUGAGCUAAACUCGAAUAUGCAAAUCUUUAUGAAAAGAUGCCCAAAAUACAGUGACUUAAACAAGUUAAGAGGUUGUUGGUGCUUUCCUCCUCUCAGAAGAGCUCAAGGGAUCCAUACUGAUUCAGGACUAGCAUGGUACUUCAAUAGAAAAAUUCCUUCCUCUCGUUUCUCUGCCAUCUUGAGAGAGUUGCCCUCAUCUUCACAGUCAAAGAUGGCUCACCAUGAUCUCAUUUCAGCCCAAGGGAAAGGAGAUGAUCUACAAGUUGUACAGAUCAUUUUCAUUUACAUCCUAUUGGCCAGAACAUGACCACAGCAAGCUUCAAGGGAGGCUGGGAAAUAAAAUGUUAGCCAGCAGACACCCUGCUAGAGCUUCUGUUACUAUAGAACAAGAUCAGCAAACAGUGGUCUGAGUGCCAAGUCAGCCAGCCAGAAAUUAUUUACAAAUUAAGUAUAGUUUGUAAAUAAAAGUGUAUUGGCCGGUUAUGGUAGCUCAUGCCUGUAACCCCAGCUCUUGGGGAGGUCAAGGCAGGAGGAUAGCUUGAGCCCAGGAGUUCAAGACAAGCCGGAGCAACAUGGUGAAACCCUGUUUAUACAAAAAUUUAAAAAAAACUAACCAGGCGUGGCUGUGCGCACCUGUCGUCCCAGCUAUUUGGGAGACUGAGAUGGGAGGAUCAGUUUAGCCCAGGAGGUCAAGACUGCAGUGAGCCAUGAUCACGCCACUGCACUCCAGCCUGGGCAACAGAGUGAUAAAUAAAUAAAAAUUAAAGUGUAUUGGAACACAGAUGUGCCCAUUUGUUUAUAAAUUACCUGCUUUCACAUGGCAGUGGAAGAGUUGAGUAUCCAAAAUGCAUGGGACCAGAAGUAUUUCCGAUUUCAGAUUUUUUUGGGAUUUUGGAAUAUUUGUGAAUACGUAAUGAGAUACCUUGGAGAAGAGAGUAAAGUCUAAUAUGAAAUUUAUGUUUCAUGUACACCAUAUGCAUAGCCUGAAGGCAAUUUUAUAUAAAUAAUAUUUUUUAUUUUUAAGACAGAGUCCUAUUCUGUCACCCAGGCUGGAGUGGCAGUGGUGUGAUCAUGGUUCACUGUAGCUUUGACCUCUUGGGCACAAGUGAUUCUCCCACUUCAGCCUCCCCAGUAGCUGGGACUAAAGGCAUGCACUACCAUGCCCAACUAAUUUUUUGAUUUUUUAUAGGGAUGAAGUCUUGCUACAUUGCCCAGGCUAGUUUCAAACUUCUGGGCUCAAGCAAUCCAUCUACCUCACCUUCCCAAAAUGCUAGGUUUACAGGCAUGAGCCACUGCGCCUGGCCCAAUUUUAUACAAUAUUUUAAAUAAUUUUGUAUAUGAAACAAAUUUUGAUUGUGUUUUGACUGCAACCUGUCAAAUGAGGUCAGGUAUGUGAAUUCUCAUUUGUAGUGUUGUGUCAGUGCCCAGAAAGUGUCAGAUUUUAGAAGAUUUUGGAUUUUCAGAUUAGUAAUACACAACAUGUAGUUGCUGCAGAGAUCAUAUGGCCUGCAAAACCUAAAGUAUUUAUUAUCUUGCCCUUUACAGAAGAUUUUUUUGUUGAUGUCUACUGUAGACAAUGGGGAAAUGAACAUGGGAGGAGCAACUGGUAGUCUCUGCCACAGUAAAGAGAAUGAUAAGAAGGGUGAAUCACUGCCUUUGAAAUGUAGAGUUAGAACUUUGUACUUAGGCAUACUAGUGGCCCAUGGGGCAGUGAGUUGGUAUGCAGGUGAUUGGUUUUUUGUUGUUGUUGUUUGUUUGUUUGUUUGAGACAGAGUUUCGCUCUUUUUGCCCAGACUGGAAUGCAAUGAUGCUAUCUUGGCUCAUCACAACCUCUGCCUCCUGGGUUCAAGCAAUUCUCCUGCCUCAGCCUCCCAAGUAGCUGGGAUUACAGGCAUGCGCCACCACGCCCGGCUAAUUUUGUAUUUUUAAUAGAGACAGGAUUUCUCCAUGUUGGUCAGGCUGGUCUCAAACUCCCAACCUCAGGUGAUCCACCUGCCUUGGACUCCCAAAGCACUGGGAUAACAGGCGUGAGCCACCAUGCCUGGCAAGUGAUUGUUGAAGAAGCAAUGUUCAGGGACAGAUUUGAGGAGCCAGGCAUGAAGUAGCCUGGUGGAGGUAAAGGGAUGAAGGCACAGAAGGCUGCUUACUGACGUGAGCUUCCAUCUUUAAAGUGGAGCAUCCUAACUCCUGGACUUUUCCCUCUUCCUGCAGCUCACUGCUCUGUCUUGCAUUCGAUUCUUGCUUAUCAGCAGUGCCACCCCUGUAGGUCAGACUCUUUCCUCCCAUUGACUUCUUACGGGUCUCCCUGCCUGGACAUUCACCCUCCUCCACAGUCACCUCCUCUAAGUGUGGCUCUUAUAUUAGUCCCAUCUCAAGAACUUCCAAGGAGUCCCUGUUACCUACUCAGUAAAGCCAAGCCUCUAAGGUCCUCCCGCUCCUUGAUCCUGAUCUUGAUCCUAUCCUGUCUUCCUUCACAGUCUUACACACACCCUAGAUUCCAGCCCAACAGAAACACCUUGUGCCUGCGCUGUACUUUGCCACCACCACGUAUUUGCUGUUGUCUCCUUGCUUCUGUCCAAAGGGUUUGGGGAUUUGGGACUAUGGCUUAGCACAUGGUAGAACAUUCAUGGCUGGGCAGAGGGGGUUUCUGACUUUGUUUUGGCAUCUCUCUACAUCUGUAUUUCCCUCUCCAGCCCCUACCCCCUUCCCUUACAACCUAAGGAUAAGCGCUCCCUUUUUGAAUGCUCCCUUUUUUAAUUAUACCAAGUACUAUAUAUAACUCCCAAGGCACUUACUGCUUUCUGUGUGGGAUUAUAGUUAUUCCAUGUAUGUUUCUAAUCUUCUUGCAGAGAAAGAAUCUGAGGCCAAGUCCAGAUCUGACUGAUCAGUUUCAUCUAGUAGGUGCCUAGUGGCUAUUUUGUUGAUCAGUGUUGCAAUGAUGGUGUCUACAAACAGUGCUACCUACAAUUUAGUGUGUUUCACUAAAAAUGUAACUUAACACCUGGAGGAAUUUAAGUGCAAAUGCAAAUAGAGGUUUUUUUGUGUGUGCGAGACAGAGUCUCGCUCUGUCGCCCAGGCUGGAGAGCAGUAGAGCGAUCUCGGCUCACUGCAACCUCCACCUCCCAGGUUCAAGGAAUUCUCCUGCCUCAGCUUCCCGAGUAGCUGGCAUUACAGACGUGCGUCAACACGCCCAGCUAAUUUUUGUAUUUUUGGUAGAGAUGGGGCUUCACCAUGUUGGCCAGGCUGGUCUCGAACUCCCGACCUCAGGUGAUCCGCCCACCUCCACCUCCCAAAGUUCUGGGAUUAUAGGCAUGAGUCACUGCGCCCGGCCUAGAGUUCUAAUAAUUGUGUUGAAAAUAAAUGCCACUUAAGAUCUUAAAAACACCAAUUUUUAGGUAGUUUUUAGCAGAAAAGAAAAAAAAAUCUAUUUAACUGUUUUCUUCAGACCUGAAGCAGUAUUUAAAUACAUUCAUAUUUAGAAGUUUUAAACAGUUCCUUGAAAAGCCAAGGCUGAGCCAGAAAUCAGGCAGAGCUUUUGCAAGGCAUAAGGAGGAGCAUGUGGGCAGAAACCCCUGUGAGUGCAAGAGGUGGGCCACCUGCAGGAAAACUGCCCAGUCCACUCUGCAGAGAAGGAUUGGAGCAUUUUCUACACCAGCCUGCCAGGGACACACCUGACUGCACAAAGAUCCAUCUAAAAUCACUCACAUUAUACUCACAGAAGGUGGUAUUUUCACAGCUUCAUCUUUCCGCAGUUGGUAAUCAAAUGUAAGAAGAGCUUUUAUUUUUAUAGGAAUGAUUUAGCUUAUGGAGUACCAAUCUCAUCCUUUUCCUUCCUCUGUCUUUUUAACCAAGCAUAGAAUGAGGAGACCAAUGUAUAUAAUCAAAUACUUGCGUAUGCUGGAAAAGAAUUUAUGUCAUUCACUCAUCUCCUUUUAAUUAAAACCUAGUGAGAUUGGUGGCAAUGUUGGGAAGCAGAUGGAUGAGCAUGAAUUUCAAAUGUGUAUUUAGAAAAAUUGAAAGGAUUGGUAGGAAAGAUAUUAAGUAGGCAGUGUGGUCGGGAGUUGAACCUGUGAGUUCAACAGCAGGCGCUUGUAGCAUAAAAUAUAGUAGUGCUUCCAGACCCCUCUGACCUAGGGAUGUCUAAGAGAUAAGGAGGGAAAGUGCAGGGGUCUCUUUUCUUGUGGUUUAUGCAUUUUGAAGUUAUUAAAGCAUAAGACAAUUUGUUCUGGAAUUUUUACUCAAGAUAAAAACUAUGACCAUUGUGUGAACAUUACUGCUUCACCUCCCUCUCCUAACUCUACUUUUGUUUACUAUUCCAUAUCCAGUGUCUAGCAGUGUACUCAUCAAACAGUAAGUGCUCAGUACAUAUUUGUUGAAUGACUAAAUAAGUGGAUUCUGGCACUUAAUUAUAAGAGCUUUUUGGAAGAUGAAAAGAUUCUUAAGCAAAAUGAUUUUUUAAAGAUGUAAAGACAAAAGAAGCUUAUCUUCCAGUCCCCUUCCUCACUUGACUCUGCCAGCCCCCUUCAAUACAUGCCUCACUGGCACCUCUCCUGGAUUUAGCUUUAAAAGUUUGGGAGGAGUGAAGGUGUGUGUCCUCAUAUUACUAAAAGAAGAACCCUAGUGUUGUGUAACAGUGUUUCACAGGCUCUUUCAUAAUAAACAUAAUAUUAGACACAGCCAAAGUAAGUUCAUUUUGAAUUAAUAAUCCAGUAUUUCAUAGUGCUGGUUCGAGGUACAGAUCUAGGCCUUGUGUGCAACAGAAUAGAAUUUUAGAAGUAGAGUAAAAAGUUUCAUCCACUAAGCUGUUUCUCAUUGGCCUGCAGUCUGAUUUCUUUCAAAGUUUUGGAGUUUAACACAAAUUUAGGUGUUCAGCUAAUAAUAAGAUUAAGGGUGUUUGUGGGCAAACCAAAUAUAAUUUAUAUCCCUUAAUUUUGAGCUCAUAAUGUUUCUGCUCUGGGUUUAUAAGAGAUACCACCGAAGAAAAAUCUCAAUUAGAGUGAGAUAAUUUGUAAAGUAAUAAGUAGGGUUUUUUUUGUUUUUUUUUUUUAGGAAGCACACUAGUGUAGUGGUUAGGUUUUUGACUUUGCAUCAUAGAGACCUGCAGUUGAUUAUUUUACCAACCUCACUACUCUUUUGUCUCAACCCUCCAAAUCUUUGUUUUUUCACCUGGAAACUGGGAAUAGUAACAGUACUUUCCUCAGAGACUCAUUAAUAAGAUAAUUCAUGUAAAACACCCAGAACAGUGCUACAUAAUAGUGUUCAUACCAGUUAUGAUUAAGCCUAUGCUGCUGGGCCAAAGAGCCCCCAAAAUACAGUGAAUUAAAGGGCAUACAACUUUUUUUAUAUUGCUCAUAUAAAAGGGUAAGCAUUCCAGGCUUGCAAAGAAUCAUGUUCUUUGCAGAAAUUCAGGCACCCAGAUUUCUUCCAUCUUGUUGCUCCAUGCUUCCUACAUCUCAGGGUUCAUCUACAUAGUCAAAGAUAGGUCGCAGGUAUGUCUGUGUCCCAGCUUGAGGGGACAGGAAGAAGUGUGGAGGCAGCAUGCGCAAUGUCUUCAUGCUCAGUCCUAGAGAAGGCACACAUCAUUGCCAUGUACUUUGCACUGGGGAGAAUUAAGUCACAUGGCCGCCCACAUCUGGCUGCCAGAGAGGCUGAGUGGUAUAAUUUCUACCUGGAUGACCAUGUGCUCAGUUACAAUUCAUUCAUUGUGGAAGAACAGAAGAACAGAUUUGGGUGAGCAGGUAAUGGUCUGCCCCACAGUGCUUAAUAAAUGCAACCAUUAUGUAUUUAUUUAAAAAUAACAUUUCAAGUAACAGUCUAAAUGUCUUUGUUCUGGGGAAGAGGAAUCAAAGAGCUUCUGUAACACAGAAUUUGUGCUACAUAGCACAUAUCUCCCAUAAGUGUUAUUUUUAUUUUUUGGAAGGGAGUCUUUUAAGUAUUGAACUUCAAAUCAAGGUAAACCUUGAGGGAGAAAAGAAAGAGUGGACAAAAAGCAGUAGAAGGGAUGGGAAUGUAUUAAAAGGAAUGAAUGCUAAUUAGCUAUAUGCUCUUCCUUCCUCUCAGCCAGCCAUCUGGGCAACAAGAAAGGCUUACUACAGUUAGAUAAAUUUAACCCCUUCUCUGACCUGGCAAGGACAAAGUACACUGGCUUCUGAAGAAACUUUUUCUUGGGAGCAAGGUAGUUAUUUCAAAGCACAGAAAAAGGCGGCGGGGGGCACAGAGAAGCACAGAGAAGCGGGGGCAGUUGCACAGGUUGUUUAUUCUGUUGAUGGAUAUUGGACUGGAGUGAUGAGUGUUCUAGGAUGGGUAUUUGAUGAUGCCAGGGGACUCAAGUAAUGGCUUUGCAUGAAGAUUACACAGUAAAGCUGCACAUUGAUUACCUCAUCUUAUUAGCUGAUGGAGAUGUUUGAGAGGACAAGAUUGCAGGGCUUUCAAGCCUGUACAGCUACCAGGAUUUGAUCCUAAGAGCUUGAUCAUUGUCAUUGCCCAUAGGGACUGUGUUAAGAAUAGUGGUGGUUUACUACUUAAACGCAUGAGAGUGUUAUAACAGUUCCCUAUGUCUUUUGAAUUGUUUAGAUAAGGUUAGGACUUUCAGAUCAACUUGAGUUUUAAUUUUUAGCAUUUAUAGAAUUCUAAAAUUAAUCCUGUUUGUUUUUGUCUUCCUCCACUAAAAUUUAAGUUUGCUGAGGUAGACAGUUUUGUUUCUGGAACCACUAUCCCUCCAGCGGCUAGAACAGUGGAACAUGUUCAAUAAAUAUUCAAUAAAUAUUUUUGAAUAAGUGAAUGAAUGAACAGGUUAAAUGUAAUCUUUAUUUUUUAAUGAACUAUCCUUUCCAGAGACAUACAAAUUGCCAGUUGAUGGCAUUUUUUAUUUCUUUUUGUAAAAAGAGUAUUUUAAAAUUUGAAUGAGUUCUAUCUAACAGAUAACACAGUUGAGUACAUUAAAAGGGACCUUGAACACAAAAUCCAUGUUUUCGUGGAUUAGUAUUUUUGCAGCUUAAAUGGUGAACGAUAGGAUUGUUAGAUGCAAAUAACUCUGGAAAUUAAAGACCUUUAGUUGUAACUCUCCCUAAAAUGUUUGUGAGAGCUUGUAAAAUGUUGUUCACUUUAUUCUAUUAUAAAAGGGCAUUAUAAUAAAUAUGAAGUUUUGAAACCAUGUUCUUUUAAAUGAGGUGAAUUAUAGAACUCUGUUAUUAGCCAUUAUGCUGUGCCCCUUCUUUUAAAGCAUAUCCCUCCACAUACCCUUUCUAAGGACUUGGGGGUAACAAAAUGAGGAGUAAGUGAAGAAAGAAGAAGGCACAGCUUGUCGAGAUUGAUGGACCGCCCCCCGCCCCCGGGAGAGCAGCGUAGGAAAUUGCAGGAUGAAAUUUGUGUGCCAGUCUUGUCAGCACCCAUUCCUGUUGAAGGAGAGGGCAUAUGGAUGAGGUGGGGAGGAUUCCAGCAGAGGGGACCCAGGAAAGGGGAGGGGGUGGGGACAACAGGAAGUGUAAUGGGAGGCUUGGGGAAAGUUGAAGAUCUGAUAAAGGUAGUUGGUGAGGUGAAGAAAGGAGAAUCCACUAAAACUUGACCCUAGGAGCAUUCUCCGCCGAAUGGCAUGGGGUAGUGACCCUGACUCUGGACAAGGAGAGAAGCAAAUGUACUCCUAGCCCUACUUGGGACCUUAAGGAAAGACUCAUCCAUGGCCAUGAUAGUGUAAAUGCUGUUUAUUGGUUUUAAGCUCUUUAACUCACCCUUUGGAGUGAAAAACAAUAGAAAGUUAAGCUGGUUACAGAACAGACUGUAAAUGUUAUAAACCUUGAAAAUGUAAACUAUAGAUACAGCAGAUGGAAAUUAGGCAGUGGAAGGGCAUGAGGAGAGAUGGGGGGAAAGGAUGAAAACUGAUUGUUCCAAGGAGCUAGAAGAUGCACUCUAAGACUGAUUAAAAAUAGCAGCUCGAUCGGGUGGCUUAAUGUCAUUCUGGUUGAGGGACUGGAAUAUGUGGUGCCACUAUAUUGGGAUAAAGCAGGAAAGUGAGAUGUCAAGACAGGACUUCAGUAGAUCUAAAAGAGGUAAGUCAUAUAUAAGCAUAUUAUUUGGAAAUAUGGGGUUUCUCUUUCAGUGUCCUGAUAAGAGACUGGAUUCAGCCCAGAUGGUUCAAAUGCAUACUUUAAUGAAUGGACUACUUAUGGUAUUAUGGGCUGGUUUACAUUCUUGGGGUUGAGGGACAGAGGAAGAAAUAAUAAAUACUAAUUUUAAAAACUGUACACAGGCUUAUUGAGCACUGAGGCAGUGGAAGAGUGGCCACUCAAGGGUGCAGUGGUCAGGGAUGUAAGGAGCCCCUGCUGGAAGCACAGGGAAUAAAUGCUCCCACUUCUGCCCAAACACAGAGAAAGGCAGAGAGUGAGUGGGGGUUAGGUAAAGCAGGGAGGGGUAAGAGAAGAAUAACCAGCAGGGAAGGUAGGUAGAACUUGGGUUGGGGUGAUCGUGUUGCCUGAUAAACUGUUCUGUACAGUUUGAUAAUCUCUUGCAGGGAGAUGGAAUAUUUUAAUGUAAAUAUUUGCAUUUAGCACCUACUAUUUCAUCUAAUGUGACAGGAGCUUGGUGGACCAGUAGUGACUUGAGCAAGAUCUCUGCCGUCAAGUAGCUUAUAGUCUGAUUGGAAAGACAAGAUGCUACCAAAACUAGCAAAAAACAAACAAAAAAAUGAUUACACAUUGUGAUUAAUGCUAUAAGUUUAAUUUCAGAGCACACAAAAAGGUUAAUCCUGCUUGUAUAAACUUAAUUCUUUAAUAAUGAUACUGCAGGCAUUUUUACAAUAUAGUUAAUUAUUUGGGAGUGGGAACAAUUCUUUUGAGUAGCCCAUUUUGCUCUAUUUAACUAUAAAUACACUACAUGCUACAAAUCAGAUGUACAGAUGAAACAGCUGCUGCUUCGUUGUUUUGUUCCUGUUACUCAUUUUAAUGAAUAAUUUGAACAGACUCCAAAACAUUAAAUUAUAUGUAUAAACAUACUUUAAGGAUUAUAUCAUAAUGUUAGUGUAUUUAAAACUUAGUGGUGAUGUCAUUACCUAAAUAUAGUAAAUUUUAAGAAAACAAAUUAUUUGAGCUAUUUUACCCUCUAUAAAUACUUUGGCAGUAAAACAGACAAGGGCUAAAAAUCAACCCAAGCAUCCAUAUCCAAGUAUAGAGAGCUGUGAAAUUCCCCCACUUUCUUCCUCCUGACAUAUGAACCUUGAUAAUUAAAAUAUAUCUUUCCAAGGUCCCUGCAUGAAAUUUGACUUUUCUUGCCUUUCUAAUGGAGAUAUGAGCAAUGGCAGAGACAGGGAAAAGGACUUAGAAGCAGAAGAGUUUUAUUCUGUCUUCCUUGAUACUUCCUGUGGCUGAAGGGUUUUGUCCAAAGGGAAAAGAUAAAUGAACAGAGGAAGAUAGAUGUAGGCUCAUUCCUCAUGCCUCCCAUCUUCCGUAGCAUUCACAGCAGUCUGAGAACAGACAAAUUCAAGUCCUGGGUUCCUAUAUCCUGAGCAUUUGCUUAUUAAAAUAAACCUUUGAAUACUUCAUCUACUCUGAUUCAGACUACUCUCUUUCCUCCAUGAAAAAGCUGGUGAGGGUGUUAUAAGCUGAUACUAUAUACAUGUAAGAUGUAGUCAUGAAUCAUUGGAAGCUCACUGCUUUUAGAACCUGCCAAAAUUACCAUACUAAUGCACUUCUAUGAAGGGUGUUAAAAUGGUAAUUAAGCAAAUAAACUCUGCUUAUUUUAGUACCUUUAUUCAUUUCAGAAUAUUUUUUGUAUGGAUCUCUCAUUUGAUUUUUACACAGUUUUUAGAAGCAGAAUUUCUGCUGUUGCAGGGGGAAGUUUUAUAUGUUCAAGUACUUAAAUAUGAGAGAAAAUCUAGAAUUGCCUCUACAAAUCAUUUUGUUUGUAAUAAUCAUGAGUUACACAUUCUGUUUGCUCUAGAAAUCAAGAAACAGAAUAGUGGAUCAUUUAAGGCCAGAAACUAUAUCCACUACUUGUAUCUCCCUUUUGGGAUGGUUUUCUGAUGUUUUUUUCAGUGUGUGUCAUUUGUAUAACCCUGGCCGGCUGUCUUGAAAAUAUAUGUCACUAAUCAUGGUAGGGGGUAGGUGGGUGAGGGGGUCAUCUGAUUGGUUGUUUACAUAAAUUAGUUGUAGUGUCUGUUAUCUUCAUAUUUAAAUAACUGUAUAUGUUAGUAUAAAACUCCAGUAUAAAAUGGGCAGCUGGCCAGGUGCUAUGGCUCACAUCUGUAAUCCCAGCACUUUGGGAAGCUGAGGCAGGAGGAUCGUUUGAGCUCAGGAGUUCGAGACCAACCUAGGCAACAUGAGGAAACCUCAUCUUUACAAGAAAAAAAAAGCAUGGAAGAGGAGAUGGUUCGUGUUACGCAGUGGCCGUUUAACUGGAGAUCCAGAUGUUUUGGAAUAUUACAAAAAUGAUCAUGCCAAGAAGCCUAUUCGUAUUAUUGAUUUAAAUUUAUGUCAACAAGUAGAUGCUGGAUUGACAUUUAACAAAAAAGAGUUUGAAAACAGCUACAUUUUUGAUAUCAACACUAUUGACCGGAUUUUCUACUUGGUAGCAGACAGCGAGGAGGAGAUGAAUAAGUGGGUUCGUUGUAUUUGUGACAUCUGUGGGUUUAAUCCAACAGAAGAAGAUCCUGUGAAGCCACCUGGCAGCUCUUUACAAGCACCAGCUGAUUUACCUUUAGCUAUAAAUACAGCACCACCAUCCACCCAGGCAGAUUCAUCCUCUGCUACUCUACCUCCUCCAUAUCAGCUAAUCAAUGUUCCACCACACCUGGAAACUCUUGGCAUUCAGGAGGAUCCUCAAGACUACCUGUUGCUCAUCAACUGUCAAAGCAAGAAGCCCGAACCCACCAGCCAAGGGUCAUCUUUUGUUUCUGAAGAAGGAGAGGAAUACCUUCUACUAGAAGAUUUUGAAAGCAAAACGAUUCCAUUGCAAACGCAUGCUGAUUCUGCAAAAUCCACCUCUUCUGAAACAGACUGCAAUGAUAACGUCCCUUCUCAUAAAAAUCCUGCUUCCUCCCAGAGCAAACAUGGAAUGAAUGGCUUUUUUCAGCAGCAAAUGAUAUACGACUCUCCACCUUCACGUGCCCCAUCUGCUUCAGUUGACUCCAGCCUUUAUAACCUGCCCAGGAGUUAUUCCCAUGAUGUUUUACCAAAGGUGUCUCCAUCAAGUACUGAAGCAGAUGGAGAACUCUAUGUUUUUAAUACCCCAUCUGGGACAUCGAGUGUAGAGACUCAAAUGAGGCAUGUAUCUAUUAGUUAUGACAUUCCUCCAACACCUGGUAAUACUUAUCAGAUUCCACGAACAUUUCCAGAAGGAACCUUGGGACAGACAUCAAAGCUAGACACUAUUCCAGAUAUUCCUCCACCUCGGCCACCGAAACCACAUCCAGCUCAUGACCGAUCUCCUGUGGAAACGUGUAGUAUCCCACGCACCGCCUCAGACACUGACAGUAGUUACUGUAUCCCUACAGCAGGGAUGUCGCCUUCACGUAGUAAUACCAUUUCCACUGUGGAUUUAAACAAAUUGCGAAAAGAUGCUAGUUCUCAAGACUGCUAUGAUAUUCCACGAGCAUUUCCAAGUGAUAGAUCUAGUUCACUUGAAGGCUUCCAUAACCACUUUAAAGUCAAAAAUGUGUUGACAGUGGGAAGUGUUUCAAGUGAAGAACUGGAUGAAAAUUACGUCCCAAUGAAUCCCAAUUCACCACCACGACAACAUUCCAGCAGUUUUACAGAACCAAUUCAGGAAGCAAAUUAUGUGCCAAUGACUCCAGGAACAUUUGAUUUUUCCUCAUUUGGAAUGCAAGUUCCUCCUCCUGCUCAUAUGGGCUUCAGGUCCAGCCCAAAAACCCCUCCCAGAAGGCCAGUUCCUGUUGCAGACUGUGAACCACCCCCCGUGGAUAGGAACCUCAAGCCAGACAGAAAAGGUCAAAGUCCUAAAAUUUUAAGACUCAAACCCCAUGGUUUAGAGCGAACUGAUUCACAAACCAUAGGUGACUUUGCUACAAGAAGAAAGGUCAAGCCAGCGCCUUUAGAAAUAAAACCUUUGCCAGAAUGGGAAGAAUUACAAGCCCCAGUUAGAUCUCCCAUCACUAGGAGUUUUGCUCGAGACUCUUCCAGGUUUCCCAUGUCCCCCCGACCAGAUUCAGUGCAUAGCACAACUUCAAGCAGUGACUCACACGACAGUGAAGAGAAUUAUGUUCCCAUGAACCCAAACCUGUCCAGUGAAGACCCAAAUCUCUUUGGCAGUAACAGUCUUGAUGGAGGAAGCAGCCCUAUGAUCAAGCCCAAAGGAGACAAACAGGUGGAAUACUUAGAUCUCGACUUAGAUUCUGGGAAAUCCACACCACCACGUAAGCAAAAGAGCAGUGGCUCAGGCAGCAGUGUAGCAGAUGAGAGAGUGGAUUAUGUUGUUGUUGACCAACAGAAGACCUUGGCUCUAAAGAGUACCCGGGAAGCCUGGACAGAUGGGAGACAGUCCACAGAAUCAGAAACGCCAGCGAAGAGUGUGAAAUGAAAAUAUUGCCUUGCCAUUUCUGAACAAAAGAAAACUGAAUUGUAAAGAUAAAUCCCUUUUGAAGAAUGACUUGACACUUCCACUCUAGGUAGAUCCUCAAAUGAGUAGAGUUGAAGUCAAAGGACCUUUCUGACAUAAUCAAGCAAUUUAGACUUAAGUGGUGCUUUGUGGUAUCUGAACAAUUCAUAACAUGUAAAUAAUGUGGGAAAAUAGUAUUGUUUAGCUCCCAGAGAAACAUUUGUUCCACAGUUAACACACUCGUAGUAUUACUGUAUUUAUGCACUUUUUCAUCUAAAACAUUGUUCUGGGUUUUCCCAAUGUACCUUACCAUAAUUCCUUUGGGAGUUCUUGUUUUUUGUCACACUACUUUAUAUAACAAUACUAAGUCAACUAAGCUACUUUUAGAUUUGGAAAUUGCUGUUUACAGUCUAACAACAUUAAAAUGAGAGGUAGAUUCACAAGUUAGCUUUCUACCUGAAGCUUCAGGUGAUAACCAUUAGCUUAUACUUGGACUCAUCAUUUGUUGCCUUCCAAAAUGCUGAGGAUAAUGUAUGUACUGGUGUCAGGACCUAGUUCUCUGGUUAAUGUACAUUUAGUUUUUAAUGGUGGAACUUUGUUAUAUUUUGUUAAUUACAGUGUUUUUGGUUCAUUGAGUGAAGAUUCUGCCGGGUGGGAUCUUGCACCUUUGAAAGACUGAAUAAUUACACUACCAAGUAAGCCUGCAAAUCAUUGAUGGCAUGCAGUGAUGAUGUGCUCUUACACUUGUUAACAUGUAUUAAGUGUUAUUUGCAAAAGGUAGAUUAUGUAACCAAUCAGGUACGUACCAGGCAGUGAUGUGCUAAUACACUGAUCAGGUUUAGACAAUGAGCUUUGGUUGUGUUCUUGUUAGUCCUAAUAUUGGUUUUCAGUUUGGAAUUAAUAAAGCAGUUGACAUUCACUGUUAGUUACAGCAACAUACUGUGAUUUUUAAUUAGAUAGUAAUUCAGAUUUAUUACUCUAUGAAAUUCUGUCUUUUGACACCAUAGUGCCCUUUCUAUGAUUUUUUUUACUUAAUAUUCUUCUUGGCCUUAUAUUUAAUUCCCUAUGCAAUUAAUAUUUUAUAUCUGCAUUUUUUUAAAAAAAAUAGAUGUUAUAUAAGUGAUUCUCGUAUGUAGCACCUGUUGCUUUUCCACUGAAAGAAUUACGGAUUUUGUACUGUGAUUUAUAUUCACUGCCCCAAUUCAAGAAAUAUUGGAGCCUUGCUACAAUGUGAAAUGUUAUAGUCAUGGACUCCUUCCAACCAGAUUUCUGAAAACACCAGAGGGAUGGUAUAAUUCUGUCUCACCUAUAACAUGGUCCUGUGACAUAGAUAUUAAGACCACAAGUUGUAGUGAGGCUACAAUUAUAUUCGUCUGUCUUGGCUUUGCAACAUAAUUUAGAAAGCACGUAUAGUUGUUUUUUAACCAAGUUACAUACAAUCUCAUGUACUGAUUUGAGACUUAUAACAAUUUUUGGAGGGGGCAUAGAGAAAGGAGUGCCCACAGUUGAGGCAUGACCCCCUCCAUUCAGACCUCUAACUGUUGCCUGAGUACACAGAUGUGCCCUGAUUUCUGGCCCAUUGGCCAUAGUACUGUGCCUAAUCAAUGUAAUAGGUUUAUUUUCCCAAUCCUCAAACUAAAAAUGUUCAUAACAAGAUGAAUUGUAGACUAGUAACAUUUGAUGCUUUUAAAUAUUUGCUUCUUUUUAAACAAAAACUAAAACCCAGAAGUGAAUUUUUAGGUGGAUUUUUAAAUAAAAAAGAUUGAUUGAGUUUGGUGUGCAAGCUGUUUUAUAAUGAAACAACAAAAUGAAAUCUAAAAUCCUGAAAUGUGCCUAAACUAUCAAAACACACGAUACAGCUAAUGUGUAAAGAUGCUAAAUUCUGUUACUUGGAGGAUGAAUAUAUUUAAGAUUUAAAACACAAUAAUAAAUACAUGAUUAAUUCAAAAAUAAAAAUCUUUACAGCUGCCUAUCAAGGGUCUAAAGCACUUAAUGAAUGUUUUUAGUCUAACUUAUCAUUAACUUUUUACAAGUCACCAUAUUUGAAGAUCUGUAGCACUCUGAUUUUCAGAAAAUUUUUCAUUCUGAAUAAUUUAAAAAUGGUGAUGUAUUAGAAAGGCAGUUUGCUUUAGAAAACUAAAUCACAUUGAACAUUGUAUUAGAGAAUUAAAUUAAAAGUUUCUUACAGAGCAGUAUUUUCCAAACAUUUUUAGCACUAGAAUCUUUUUAGAUGAAAUUUUAUGUAUAACCCCAAUACAUAAAGCCUGAAAACUCAAUUUUAUCAAUAUAAAUGUAUUUUGGGUUCACAUUUAUGCUUAUUCAUUUUGGCUCAUUACUAAGCAUAAUAAGAUUCUGAGUUAUUUCUGAAUAACACAAAUGUGGAGUUAUACAUAGUUGAUGAAACCAGCAGCCAAUUUAUAGCUAUGCCCUGUUUUAUUUGUAUACUAUCAAGAAAAUUUUGAUUCACACAAAUGUAAGCAAAAAUAAUAGGUUUUAAACAUACAUCUCAGGAAAUUCUUUAAUUAGAGAUAGCUAAAGUUAUUCAAGGUCUAUACAAAAAUAAGUUAUCCUGGUAGUGGAAGUUAAUACAUAAGCAGUCUCCAGUGUGGUAAAGUAGGGUAUGUAACACAUCAGAAUGUGCGUUUUUAUUAGGUUUUAAAAUAUGCACGUAUAAAAACUAAAUUUGAAUCAAACCCUUUUAACUCACCUCCAAGAAGCUAGACUUUGGCCAGGAAUGGGCUAAAAACCACUGGUUAACGAUGUGACAGUUAUGAUCUUGGAGAUUGGAAAUCUUUCUUCCACAUUAGAGUUCUUUACCUUAAUUCCUUAUUCUGAAAAAUUGUAAGAUUUUAUGAAGGUUUGAAUACUGAAGCACAGUUCUGCUUUCAAAAAUUAAAAUUCAAACUUGAAAAAGCUGUUUAACCCAUGGAAGAUAUCAUUUAGUAAGAUGUAAAAGAUUUUUUAAAUCUACACUUCAGUUUAUACAUCUUUAUCAUUAUCAAUACUAUAUAAGUUACUGUGAGCAUUUUAGAGAAUUCCAUAAAGGUACUAUGAGUGUGUCUGUAUGUGUGUGUAUAUAUAGCAUUGUAUUUAAUCAUAGACUAAAUUUAAUUUGAUAUAGAAAUACUACUUUACUUGUACAUUAAGGUCAUAAUUUCUGCUGGACUCUUUUAUAUUUAAUUAAUGGGGAUUAUAGUCUUCCUUCAUAAAUGCAUUUAAACCUGAAAUUGAACACCAGUGUUUUUCUUUUUCUACUUAUGGGAAGUUGUCUGCUUCCCCCUUUAGAGAAAACAGUAUUUUUAUAUUUUGUUAAAAUAUUAACUACUUUAUGCCUACACACUAUGCUGUAGAUACUGAUCAUAAUUCUUGGGUGUUCACAAACACUCCUAGUGCCUCUUUUUUGGCCCGUUGAAAGUGUUGGUAUUACUACUUUCACUACAGAGCCUUUGGCCCUCUAAUAAUGCUGAGGUGGGCUGAUCCUUCCCAUUUCUGUCUUCGGGUCAUUCUGGUAGGUCUUCUCCUCCACUGUCAAGUAAGCAAUCAGGUCCGUGACAGGGAUUGGACAUAUGAACAAAUUAAGUGGAUACACACAGUGAGAAAGAUACAUGCAUUCUAUGGUAACAACUACUGUCAAUAACAUCUGAUGUUACAUGCACAUUUAUAUAUAUAUAAUUUUAAAAACUGAACUAUGAGAAGCCAUGGUAUAAAUGAAUAUUGUGGACAUCAUGGACUUGAUAUGAUAGAAAUCAAUUGUCAGCUUGAGAAAGUUGUUUUUAAUCUGUCUAAAUAGUUCAUGCAUUACUACAGUUAAAAAUAGUUUCAUUUGUCUUCUAUAGACUUAAUUUUAUUCCGGUUCAGUAUAAUCUCUGUUAACAGAGUUUCAGCAAACUGAUUGGUCAAGGUAUUAACAUAGCUUCUACUUCCUUUACUUAAAAAGAUGUGGUUUUAUGUAAGUUCUUGAUUACUGAUGAUCAUCCCAAAUUUUGACAACAAAAUCAUAUGUAUAAAUUUAUUUCUCCCCUCUUGUUCAUCAUCUUUUGUAAAGGUCCCAUUGUAGAUCUUUUCUGCUACCAAAUAAAACUUUUCAAACAAUUUGGUUUCAAGACCUUAAAUAGACAAGUUGGAUACUAAGAUUGUGAACUGAUAAGGACAUAUAAAUUUAUAUUUCCAGCCCUUCCUUAGAGUCUUUAUCUGCAUCAAAAACCCAAUUCUGCCAUUAACUGUGCUUCCCAGUCCCACCUCUAUAUGUCACUCAUUUUCUGCAACAAAGAUCUCACUAAAUCAUGUUGAAACACAAGUCAUGAUCCUCUCUAAGUAAAUAGAAAAAGCUCCCUGGAAAAACUCUGUUGCCACAUGCACGUGCCCUGUUACUCCUCCAGCCAGCCAGUGCUGCCAGCAUUUUAUUGUGUAAAAGUCCAAAUAAAUAAGGGCCUGCAUGCAACCUUUAUCUUCAGAAACUAGGUUUUAUAUGUAAAAUGUGACUUGGGAAAUGAUUCUGUUUAUUAACUGGCUGGGAUUUUUCAUUUCUAUGAAAGUUUCAAACAUCUCCAGUACUUUAUAAAAUCCCAACAAUUGCUGUAAGUCAGCACUUUGGUCCACUCAGCCCACCCAGCCCACUUGCAACUCUGACUCUUCACUGAAUCAUAUUUGGGAAGUUUGGGUAGGGUGAGGCUAUCUUCUUCAAGAUUAUUUUCUCAUAUGUCUGUCUGUCACCUUGUAAACCAUGAGACUCCUGGGUAUUUGCAUGUAACUUCUUUGAGGAAGUUACCACCAUCUCUGAUAUAGACACACUUUUUGAGUUGCAGUUUCUGUUAGAAUUUUUUGGAGACUAACUUGCCAAUUCUGUGAAUGUUAUUGAAUAUUUAAAAAGCUGGGUCUGUAAUGGGAGGCAUUUUAUUAGCUGUUGUGAUUGGGUAACAUGUCCCCUUAGAUUUCCUGAUUUAAAAUUAUACAAAAUUACUAUUUUUGAUAAAAUAAAGGAACACCUACAGAAAAUUAAGUUUCUAAGAUGUUUCUAUACUUCAUUAGAAAAGAUUUUAUUACUAUUACUUAUGGUUAUUGGUGAUUAACACUUAAUGCGUCUCCUCUGAUUUUGUGUUCCAUGAGGUGCUUGGAACAUUUGGAGUGCUCUGUGCGAGGGACAUACAGUGAUAUAGGAAAUUUAAAAAUUAAAAUAAUACCCAAAACCCACUUUAUCAGAUAUGGUAUUGUGAUGGUUAAUAUUAUGUGUCAACUUGGUGAGGCUAUGGCGCCCAUGUGUUUGGUCAAACACUAGCCUAGAUGUUGCUGUGAAUAUAUUUUGUAGAUGUGAUUAACAUUUACAAUCAGUUGAUUUUAAGUAAAGCAGAUUCUCAUCCA